AAUGUUGCUGAAUGAAUGAAUAAAUGAAUGAAUGAAUGGGUGGAUCUUUGAGACGGAAAAGGUCUUAGAUUCUUCUAGUCCAACCUUGCCAUUGUACAGAUUGGAAAUCUGAGGCCCAGGGAGGAUAAGAGACUUACUCAGGGUCACAGAGAGUGACUGGCAAGGUUGGGGCUUGGAGCACGGCCUCACCAGCAUCUAGCCUCGUCGCUUGGGAAGCAUUUUCAGAAUUUUUCCUCAGUAGCCAGGUCUGAGCUCUAAGCUGCGGGGGCCCUGAGGACGCAAAGCCUGGCCCCUGCACCCCCUGGAUUGGAACAGCAGGUGACCUCUGUUACCUACGUGGAGGCCACUCAGGGGGUCACCAGAGACAGGCCAGGCUGGUGUGUGCCUACGCGGGGAACAGAAGGCCCAUGUUGGGGCCUGGGGCUGGAAGUAGAACCUGAAGCGUGGGUUGGGGCAAGGGCAGCAGAAGCAAAUGCCUACAGGGGAGUCCACGUGGCCUUCCUGAGCCUCAGAGCGGGGUGCAGGAGCUGGGUAAGGCUGGCCGACCUGAAUUCCUUCCUCCCCUCACAUGCUCCUGGGGGACCCAGCCGCACGCAAACUCGAAUCUUCCGGAAGCAGCAGCUGUUUGAGGCUUGGGCACUUCCUGCUUUCUGGGGUACAGGGUUCAGGGGAUGACACGGAGAGCUGACCAGCAGGACUGUGCACUCCCUCCCCCACUCCCUGUCCCCUUUCAGCUGCCUUAGCCCUCAGAGGGGGAGGGACUGCUUUUCAUGAGGCCUUGAGCCAGGUACUAGGGGCAUGGGGGCUCCCUGUACCUCGAAGGUCUUAUCUGAAAGCGAGCCUGGAUUGUUCUGCUUAAGGUCAAAGCAGAGAGUACAAGGAGAGGGCGCAGGUUCGCGCAGCGGGGACUUUCUAGAACCCCAAGACGACGGUAGUGGCCGUGUAUUGAGCAGUACUGAGCACCUACUGUAUGCCGGGCUCUGUUCUGGGCACUGGGAUGUAGGUGACUUUGAACAGCUUCCGGAUGAUGUUGCCAUCUCGGCCAACAUUGCUGACAUCGAGGAGAAGAGAGGCUUCACCAGCCACUUUGUUUUCGUCAUCGAGGUGAAGACAAAAGGAGGAUCCAAGUACCUCAUCUACCGCCGCUACCGCCAGUUCCAUGCUUUGCAGAGCAAGCUGGAGGAGCGCUUCGGGCCAGACAGCAAGAGCAGUGCCCUGGCCUGUACCCUGCCCACACUCCCAGCCAAAGUCUACGUGGGUGUGAAACAGGAGAUCGCCGAGAUGCGGAUACCUGCCCUCAACGCCUACAUGAAGAGCCUGCUCAGCCUGCCGGUCUGGGUGCUGAUGGAUGAGGACGUCCGGAUCUUCUUUUACCAGUCGCCCUAUGACUCAGAGCAGGUGCCCCAGGCACUCCGCCGGCUCCGCCCGCGCACCCGGAAAGUCAAGAGCGUGUCCCCACAGGGCAACAGCGUUGACCGCAUGGCAGCUCCGAGAGCAGAGGCUCUAUUUGACUUCACUGGAAACAGCAAACUGGAGCUGAAUUUCAAAGCUGGAGAUGUGAUCUUCCUCCUCAGUCGGAUCAACAAAGACUGGCUGGAGGGCACUGUCCGGGGAGCCACGGGCAUCUUCCCUCUCUCCUUCGUGAAGAUCCUCAAAGACUUCCCUGAGGAGGACGACCCCACCAACUGGCUGCGUUGCUACUACUACGAAGACACCAUCAGCACCAUCAAGGACAUCGCGGUGGAGGAAGAUCUCAGCAGCACUCCCCUAUUGAAAGACCUGCUGGAGCUCACAAGGCGGGAGUUCCAGAGAGAGGACAUAGCUCUGAAUUACCGGGACGCUGAGGGGGAUCUGGUUCGGCUGCUGUCGGAUGAGGACGUAGCGCUCAUGGUGCGGCAGGCUCGUGGCCUCCCCUCCCAGAAGCGCCUCUUCCCCUGGAAGCUGCACAUCACGCAGAAGGACAACUACAGGGUCUACAACACGAUGCCAUGAGCUGACGGUGUCCCUGGAGCAGUGAGGGGACACCAGCAAAAACCUUCAGCUCUCAGAGGAGAUUGGGACCAGGAAAACCUGGGAGGAUGGGCAGACUUCCUGUCUUUGAGGCUAAUGGACCCGUGGGGCUUGUAAUCUGUCUCUUUCUACUAUUUACAUCUGAUUUAAAUAAACCAUUCCAUCUGAAAGGGG